AGUUUGGCCCCGUUUGUAAAAGGCCGCGGCAGGCGAAGAGAGAAGAGGUGAGGGCGGUCGUCAGCUAAGGGCCCCGGGGCUCGCGGGGGGUGCGCAGGGCAGGUAAGGGGGUAGUGCUGAGCAAGGACCGGGGCGGCGGUGGGGCAGGGGUGUAGAGCUCGGGUUCCCAGCGGAAAGCAUGUCCAAGGAGCGGCUGCCGGCGAGGUGAUGCUUCUGCCUGGGCCUACUUGGGACCGGAAGUGAGCGCUCGCGCGGGGAGGAUGCCGGGAAGCAGGUCCCAGGGGAUAUGUGUGUGUCGCUGCAGACCCAUCCCGGAAGCCGGCCGGGAGGUGAGCGUCCCGGAGUCGGGCGGCCGCUCCGUUGACUGCAGGGCCCCGGCGGUCUUCCUCCGCUGUUCCGAGGCCGUUGAGGGCUGAUGUGCUCCAUCCUCCCACUUGUGGUUUGGCAAGCCAUCCAGCCGACUACAAACCCACGUUUGUGAGUUACCUGCUGGCUGUGACGCUUCCGUCAAAUCUGAGUAACAGUUUCCUCAUCUCUAAGAUGGGUAACAUAGUAUCUACCUCACAGGAUCGUGUGGGCAGUACAUGCAUAGAAAGGAUUUAACACGCAGUGUACUCAGCUAGUUUUAUUAUUUAUCCGUAAUGAUCAUUUGUUCUUUUCCCCUAACUGUGCCUCACAAGCAUGAAACAGAAUCCACCAAACAUUUAGGUCUGGGUAGUGGUUGGAUGGAAACCCAUCGCGGGUUAACGCUUCCAACACCAGUCCCUUGACACUCUCCCGCCGAGGAGGCUGAUUUGUAAACUUGCUGAGAAGAGAAUACCCAGCAGAUCUUUCAGACUAUCAAGAUCUCCACUUAGGGAAGUGGGAAUCUUAUUUGCGGAACAUUGGGCAGAAGCUUUGCCAUUGGCUGGUGGAGAAGGAGGAGGCAGAAUGUCUGCAUUGUUACACCAUACAGCUCAAACUUCAGAAGAUUUUGGGUUAAGCAGUUAUCAUUAGUCUGCAAAUGAUCGUGUUUUCACCUGAUCAUUAGAAACUAAUGAAACACCUUUUAAGUCUUAUGAAUUCAGGUUACACUGUUUUCCAGAUGCCUUGGCAGCUGGUACAGGGCCUCUGAAAAAUGGAACCAAAUUCUCUGAGGACUAAAGUCCCAGCUUUCUUAUCUGAUUUGGGGAAGGCCACAUUGAGGGGAAUCAGAAAGUGUCCCCGAUGUGGCACAUACAAUGGAACCCGGGGACUGAGCUGUAAGAACAAGACAUGUGGAACCAUAUUCCGCUACGGUGCACGCAAGCAGCCUAGUGUUGAAGCUGUCAAAAUCAUUACAGGCUCUGAUCUUCAGGUCUACUCAGUGCGGCAAAGAGACCGGGGCCCUGAUUACCGAUGCUUUGUGGAGCUCGGGGUUUCAGAGACAACAAUCCAGACAGUGGAUGGGACGAUCAUCACUCAGCUGAGCUCUGGACGGUGUUAUGUCCCCUCAUGCCUGAAAGCUGCCACUCAAGGCGUUGUGGAAAACCAGUGCCAGCACAUCAAGCUGGCGGUGAACUGCCAGGCAGAGGCCACCCCUCUGACCCUGAAGAGCUCGGUCCUGAAUGCAAUGCAGGCCUCCCCGGAAACCAAACAGACCAUCUGGCAGUUGGCCACGGAACCCACAGGUCCUCUGGUGCAGAGAAUUACUAAAAACAUCUUGGUGGUGAAAUGCAAGGCAAGCCAGAAGCACAGUUUGGGGUAUUUGCAUACAUCUUUUGUGCAGAAAGUCAGUGGCAAAAGCUUGCCUGAGCGCCGCUUCUUCUGCUCCUGUCAGACUCUGAAAUCGCACAAGUCAAAUGCCUCCAAGGAUGAGACAGCCCAGAGAUGCAUUCAUUUCUUUGCUUGCAUCUGUGCCUUUGCCAGUGAUGAGACACUGGCUCAGGAAUUCUCAGACUUCCUAAAUUUUGAUUCCAGCGGUCUUAAAGAGAUUAUUGUACCCCAGUUAGGUUGCCAUUCAGAAUCAACAGUAUCUGCUUGUGAGUCUACUGCCUCUAAGUCAAAGAAGAGGAGAAAGGAUGAAGUAUCUGGUGCACAGAUGAACAGUUCACUACUGCCUCAAGAUGCAGUGAGCAGUAAUCUAAGGAAAAGUGGCCUGAAAAAGCCUGUGGUUGCUUCCUCGUUAAAAAGGCAGGCCUGUGGUCAGCUGUUAGAUGAGGCACAAGUGACUUUAUCCUUCCAAGACUGGCUGGCCAGUGUCACAGAACGCAUCCAUCAAACCAUGCACUAUCAGUUUGAUGGCAAACCAGAACCAUUGGUGUUCCACAUUCCUCAGUCAUUUUUUGAUGCCCUGCAACAAAGAAUAUCUAUAGGAAGUGCAAAAAAACGGCUCCCCAACUCCACCACAGCUUUUGUUCGGAAAGAUGCCUUGCCACUGGGAACCUUUUCCAAGUAUACUUGGCAUAUCACUAAUAUCCUGCAAGUUAAACAAAUCUUAGAUACCCCAGAGAUGCCCUUGGAAAUCACCCGUAGCUUUAUCCAGAACCGAGAUGGGACUUAUGAGCUAUUUAAAUGCCCUAAAGUGGAAGUAGAAAGCAUAGCAGAAACCUACGGUCGUAUAGAAAAACAACCAGUGCUGCGACCCUUGGAACUAAAAACUUUUCUCAAAGUUGGCAACACUUCCCCAGAUCAAAAGGAGCCAACACCUUUCAUCAUCGAGUGGAUCCCAGAUAUCCUUCCCCAAUCUAAGAUUGGCGAGCUGCGGAUCAAGUUUGAGUAUGGCCACCACCGGAAUGGGCAUGUGGCGGAGUACCAAGACCAGCGGCCCCCCUUGGACCAGCCCUUGGAACUGGCCCCUCUGACCACUAUUACUUUCCCUUAAAGCAAAACAAGAUAAUAAUCUUUUGCUGCUUAAUUUGCACAUCCCCACCCCUUGACAACUUUAAAUGCUAGUUAGGCACUUAGAUGGCCCUGUUCCUUGGUAAACUGCUCUUAGCUAAGAUGCAAAUUCUCAGUGCUUUCAAGUGGAUUCUGUUGAAGAAAAUCUCUUGUAAAUAGCCUUUUUGAUGCUGCUGUGUACAGUCUUCAUUAUGCAUUGGGCAGUAUUUCUGGCUAGAGUUUUAAAAGGAACAGAAAGAAAACCAGCUUAUUUUCCUUCUUACGGACUCAUCUUUAGCGUUUAUUUCAACCUUUUGCUAAUUCUCUGAGAAAUCUGCAGCACUCAGCCAUACACCAACAGUGUUGGAAAGUUAACACCCUGGUUAGGGCAGAAUGUUAAAGACCAUCUUGGCAGAGUUCCAGCCACGCUCUUUAUUCUGUUCUCAAAUAAAGCAGUGUCACUAGUUUUUCCUAA